GUAGUCGCCGCGUCGCCGGUGCGGCCGCCAUUGUCCGGCGUUCGGCGAGUCGGGUGGUCCCUUUGGCUGGAGUGCCUCUCUGGUCUGGGGAUCACCUCAGGCGCUGUCCUUCACUGGGCGAUCCAGCAUGGACCCCGAGGACGAAGGGGUAGCGGGAGUGAUGUCUGUGGGGCCGCCGGCGGCCCGGCUUCAGGAACCAGUGACCUUCCGGGAUGUGGCUGUGGACUUUACCCAGGAGGAAUGGGGGCAGCUGGACCCUACCCAGAGGAUCCUCUACCGUGACGUGAUGCUGGAGACCUUUGGUCACCUGCUCUCCAUAGGUCCUGAGCUUCCGAAGCCUGAAGUCAUCUCCCAGCUGGAGCAAGGGACCGAGCUAUGGGUGGCUGAGAGAGGAACCACCCAGGGCUGCCAUCCAGCCUGGGAGCCUCGAUCUGAAAGCCAAGCAUCACGCAAGGAAGAGGGCCUGCCUGAAGAGGAGCCAUCCCAUGUCACGGGAAGGGAAGGAUUCCCGACAGAUGCUCCUUAUCCCACCACGUUAGGGAAAGACAGGGAGUGUCAGAGCCAGAGUCUGGCACUCAAGGAGCAGAAUAACUUGAAGCAGUUGGAAUUUGGCCUCAAGGAAGCACCAGUUCAAGAUCAAGGCUACAAAACUCUCAGACUCAGGGAAAACUGCGUCCUGAGUUCAAGCCCAAAUCCAUUCCCAGAGAUCUCUAGAGGGGAGUAUUUGUAUACUUACGACUCACAGAUUACAGACUCAGAACAUAACUCCAGCUUAGUCAGUCAGCAGACAGGCUCCCCAGGAAAACAGCCCGGUGAAAACAGUGACUGUCACAGAGAUUCCAGUCAGGCCAUUCCAAUUACGGAACUCACAAAAAGCCAGGUGCAGGACAAACCCUACAAAUGUACUGACUGUGGGAAGUCGUUUAACCAUAACGCACACCUCACCGUGCACAAGAGGAUUCAUACGGGAGAAAGACCUUAUAUGUGCAAGGAGUGUGGGAAAGCCUUCAGCCAGAACUCCUCCCUCGUCCAGCAUGAGCGCAUCCACACUGGAGACAAGCCCUACAAGUGUGCCGAAUGUGGGAAGUCUUUCUGCCAUAGUACACACCUUACCGUCCAUCGGAGGAUUCACACUGGGGAGAAGCCCUAUGAGUGUCAGGACUGUGGGAGGGCCUUCAACCAGAACUCCUCCCUGGGGCGGCACAAGAGGACACACACUGGGGAGAAGCCAUACACCUGCAGUGUGUGUGGGAAAUCCUUCUCUCGGACCACUUGCCUUUUCCUGCACCUGAGAACUCACACCGAGGAGAGGCCCUACGAGUGUAACCACUGCGGGAAGGGCUUCAGGCACAGCUCAUCCCUGGCCCAGCACCAGCGGAAGCACGCGGGGGAGAAGCCCUUUGAGUGCCGCCAGAGGCUGAUCUUUGAGCAGACGCCAGCUCUCACAAAGCAUGAAUGGACAGAAGCCCUGGGCUGUGACCCACCUUUGAGUCAAGAUGAGAGGACUCACCGAAGCGACAGACCCUUCAAAUGUAAUCAGUGUGGGAAGUGUUUCAUUCAGAGCUCUCACCUCAUCCGGCACCAGAUAACUCACACCAGAGAGGAGCAGCCCCAUGGGCGAAGCCGGCGGCGUGAACAAUCCUCGAGCAGGAACUCACACCUGGUUCAGCAUCAACACCCGAACUCCAGAAAGAGCUCUGCAGGCGGAGCAAAGGCAGGGCAGCCGGAAAGCAGAGCCCUGGCUUUGUUUGACAUCCAAAAAAUCAUGCAAGAGAAAAACCCUGUGCACGUUAUUGGGGUGGAAGAGCCUUCUGUGGGUGCUUCCAUGUUAUUUGACAUCAGAGAAUCCACAUAGGAGAGAAACUUUGCUGAUGACUUUUAACCACAAGUAAAAAAUGUGGUAAGUCCACAUAGUGUACUCAUGGAAGGAGGGGCUGGGGGUAGAAAUGUCAUGGGUGACUUCUGACUUUCUAAGGAAAUGAUGCUUCCCAAGCACCCGAGGUUGGUUGGUCCCAAAUCUAUCAAACUCAGUGCCCUCUUUAGCGACAUAUUUUGUGACAUUCCUUCCAUUACACCACAGUGAGUUCACAGGUAAUAUAACCUACCCACCUGUGUAAUGUCAAAAAAAAUCAAUAUGCGGCCCCAUUUUGUAAAGGAUCAUUAAAAUGAAAGUAAUUUAUGGUAGAGUAAAUUGUAGAGUAACGUGUACUGACUUGGUGCAGUAUUUCUCCUUGUCACUGUGGGCCCAAUUUUGCCAGGAGACCUAGGGCAAUAGCCUGUUGCUUGUGGACUGGUAGAGGGUAUGAUGUUGACCAUGGCAAUACUGUGAGGGGCCUUCCCAUGUGGAACGUGACCUUCCAAAGUAGUGACUAACUCUUGGAAAAGUUUUUAACAACAUAAUAUGCUAUUGCAUUUCUGGGAAAUUCUGGGUAAAUUCCAAGCAUGCAGCAAUUAGUUUGUGCUUAUGUGUGAAGUCCAGUUAGGUUCUCAGUUCAUACCCUGAAAACUGCUUAUUCCACAUCUGUUGAUGUGGUCCACUGGGGGCAGUUCUGUUCCUCACCAUCUUGGCAGCAUGCAUGGCUCCUGCCCACAUUUCAACCACACCCCCAACCCAAUUACGUGACCAGCCCCCACGAAAUUUCACAGCAUUCCGUGCAGGGGAGUGUCACAGCUCCUCUUGAAAAACAUCUGGUGUUGCUAUGAGCCAGAAGUUCUUUUUUUUGUUUUUUGUCUGAGAUGGAGUCUCGCUCCGUCACCCAGGCUGGAGUGCAAUGGCGCAGUCUGCUCACCACAACCUCCGCCUCCCAGGUUAAAGCAAUUCUCCUGCCUUAGUCCCCCGAGUAGCUGGGAUUACACGCACCUGCCACCACGCCCAGCUAAUUUUUGUAUUUUUGGUAGAAAUGGGGUGUUGGCCAGGCUGAUCUCAAACUCCUGACCUCGUGAUCCACCCACCUCGGCCUCCCAAAGUGCUGGGUUUACAGGCAUGAGCCACUAUGCCCAGCUGAGCCAGAGGUUCUUAACUGGUGGUGCUUUUGCCUCCAGGGCACAUUUGGUGACAUCUAGGGACAUUUUUGGUUGCUGUGCCUGGAGGAAGGGUGCCGCCGUCAUGUAGUGGGUAGAGGCCAGGGACGCUGCUCAACAUCCUUUAGUGCCCGGGACAGCUCCUCAACAAAGGAUUCUCUAGCUCAAAUGUCAAUAGUGCCAAGGUGGAGAAGCCACCUGGGUAUAAACCCAGCCCAGAAAUGUAGCUGACAUUUUUAAAACUUGCAGCCAGCUGUGGUGGCUCACGCUUGUGAUCCCAGCACUGUGGGAGGCUGAGGAGGGCGGAUCCUUUGAGGUCAGGAGUUUGAGACUAGCCUGGGCCCAUGGCGAAACCCCAUCUCUACUAAAAAUACACAAAUUAGCCAAGUGUGGUGACAUGCGCCUGUAAUUCUAGCUACCUGGGGGAGGCUGAGGCACGAGAAUCGCUUGAACCUGGGAGGCAGAGGUUUCAGUGAACCGAGAUUGCACCACUGCACUCCAGCCUGGGUGACAGAGCAAGACUCUGUCUCAGAAAAAAAAAAGAAAAGAAAAAAAACCUUCAAAUUGAUUAAUCAGGGCUGGACUAGACUAGAAAUCAUAUAAGCUUGAUUUUAACAGAUGGCAUCAUUAGCUAGUUUAUACAUGAUGUACUUUUUAGUACAUCCUUUACGGUUUUGCAGCAUUCAUAAUUGAUGUGAAAUAAGGAAGAUAAUCCUUUUUUUUUUUUUGAGACAGAGUCUCACUCUUUUGCCCAGGCUGGAGUCAGUGUUGUAAUCACUGCUCACUUGGCAGCCUCGACCUCCUGGGCUCAAGUGAUCCUCCCACCCCAGCCUCCCAAGUAGCUGGGACCACAGGCAUGUGCCACCAUUCCUGAUUUUUUUUAUUUUUUGCAGAGACAGGGUCUCACUGUGUUGCCUAGGCUGGUCUCGAACCUUGGCGUCCCAAAGUGUUGAGAUUAUAGGCAUGAGCCACUGUGCCCAGCCACUUAUUUUUCUGAGUAACCUUUAAGGAUGUAUUGUGGACAUUUUCAAACAUGAGUCAUAUAUUUUUGCUGGUACUCCCAUCUACCUCCCCACCAUUCUCCUUCCCUGGAUAUAUAUAUAACCAUGUUUGUCCACUGGGACAAAACCAUUUUCACAAUCAUACUAAGCUGUCAUUUCACAUUUUUGCUGUGCACUGAUAGUGUGAAAGCAAUGGCAGGUAAAACUGCUGAGCCUGAGUUCAAAGCAGGGCAGUAGCCCUGAGGUUGGUUGUUCAUAUUCUUCUCCACUGGGAAAUGCAGUAAAGAAAAAGAAAAGCUAAUUUCACUUAAUUUCUUUUCUUUUCUUUUUUUUUUUUUUCUUUUGAGACGGAGUCUCGCUCUGUCGCCCAGGCUGGAGUGCAAUGGCGUGAUCUCGGCUCACUGCAACCUCCACCUCCACGGUUCACGCCAUUCUCCUGCCUCAGCCUCCCGAGUAGCUGGGACUACAGGUGUGCGCCAUCUUGCCCAGCUACUUUUUUGUAUUUUUAGUAGAGAUGGGGUUUCACCAUGUUAGACAGGAUGGUGUCGAUCUUCUGACCUCAUAAUCCGCCCACCUCGGCCUCCCAAAGUGCUGGGAUUACAGGCAUGAGCCACUGCGCCUGGCCCUCUUUUUCUUUUUGAGAUGGAGUAUUGCUCUGUCGCCCAGGCUGGAGUGCAGUGGCACAAUCUUGGCUCACUGCAACCUCCGCCUCCCGGGUUCAAGCAGUUCUCAUGCUUCAGCCCUCUAAGUAGCUGGGAUGACAGGUGUGCGCUACCACACCCGGCUAAUUUUUGUAUUUUUAGUAGAGAUGGGGUUUUACCAUGUUGGCCAGGCUGGUCUCAAACUCAUGACCUCAAGUAAUCUGCCCGCCUCAGUCUCCCAAAAUGCUGGCAUUACAGGCAUGAGCCACCGUGCCUGGCCUACUUUCACUGAAUUUCUGUGAUGAAACGGGAAAAAUUAAUUUUGUUAAAUCUCAAGUAGAACUAUAUUGUCAUUAUCACAUCUAAACAGAUAUCAUCAAAUACCUAGUGUUCAGAUGUUCUGGGUUGCCUCAUAAAUUUUGUUUUCUAUUUGUUUCAUAGUAAUCAUAAUCUAAACAAGAUCCACACAGUGCAUUUGGUUGGAAUUUUUCUUUUUUCUUUUUCUUUUUUUUUUUUGUGAUGGAGACUUGCUCUGUCACGUGGUUCACUGCAACCUCCCAGGUUCAAGCAAUUCUCCUGCCUCAGCCGCCCCUGUAGCUGGGACUGCAGGCAUGCACCACCACACUCAGCAGAUUUCUUAAUUGUUUGUAGAGAUGGGGUUUUACUACAUUGCCUAGGCCAGUUUCAAACUGGGCUCAAGCGAUCCUCCCACCUUGGCCAUCCAAAGUGCUAGGAUUACAGGUGUGAGCCAAUGCACCCUGCCAAACAGCAAUUUUUUUUUUUUUUGAGACAGAGUCUCGCUGUGUCACCCAGGCUGGAGUGCAGUGGUGCGAUCUCGGCUCACUGCAAGCUCCGCCUCCCAGGUUCAUGCCAUUCUCCUGCCUCAGCCUCCCGAGUAGCUGGGACUACAGGCGCCCGCCACCACGCCCGGCAAAUUUUUUGCGUUUUUAGUAGAGACGGGGUUUCACCCUGUUAGCCAGGAUGGUCUCAAUCUCCUGACCUCGUGAUCCACCUGCCUCGGCCUCCCAAAGUGCUGGGGUUACAGGAGUGAGCCACCGCGCCUGGCCCCAAAACAGCAAUUUGAAUAACCAUGUUGGAAUGGUUGAGCAUUGGAACGCAUUAGCAUCAGAACUUCCCGUGUCAGGCCAGGCGCGGUGGCUCACGCCUGUAAUCCCAGCACUUUCGGAGGCCGAGAUGGGCAGAUCACGAGGUCAGGAGAUCGAGACCAGCCUGGCUAACACGGUGAAACCCUGUCUCUACUAAAAAUACAAAAAAUUAGCCUGGCGUGGUGGCGGGCGCCUGUAGUCCCAGCUACUCGGGAGGCUGAGGCGGGAGAAUGGCGUGAACCUGGGAGGCAGAGCUUGCAGUGAGCUGAGAUAGUGCCUCUGCACUCCAGCCUGGGUGACAGAGCUAGACUCCAUCUCGAAAAAAAUAAAAGAACUUCCCGUGUCCGUUUUUGCUUUUUGGAUGCUGGGAGUGUCACAACUCAGCUAUCCAAUCAAGGCAGAGCUGGCCUCCAGGAUGCCAGAGCCAGAGCUUUGUGGUUCAUCUCUAGAGGUUCAACAGGACCCUGUGGAUGGCCCAAGUUCGUUUCUCUGCACUUACCUCUUCGGGGUUGUCCUCAAAACGUUGCCGUGUCAGCUCUCACUUUUCACAGCAACUCUGGCCUCCUACCUUGGACUGCGCCACUUCUGUCUCCUUAGAUAACCUCCAUUCGCAUAGCUAAAUGCUGCACCCUCCGACACUGCCACAAUAAUAGUUCUGUGAGUUAGUACCAUUUUAUAGAUAGGCAAAAUUUGGCACAGGACAAAAGUUAGUGGUAACUAGAACAAAAGUAACCAGCCCAAGCUAGGAAGUGGUGGAGUUAGAAUUUGAUGUCAGCACCCAGCUGACCAUGGCUUAAACAGAUGAGGCUUUGUUCAAAGGCUGUCUUUUCAGUGGCUCAGCUGUGUCACAGUCGAUGUUUUCUGCAAUCUCUCAACCUUUCCAUUGUGGUCAUGAGGAGACUCCUAUGGCUCCAGCCAUUGCAUCCACAGUGAAGACUGAAAGAAGGGGGAAUGGGCAGGCCAACACUUACCGCUGAUGGUGUUUAAAGGAAAAACAUUCCCAGAAGCCUGCAGCACAUGCCCCCCUUAGUCUCACUGGCCACAGAUGGGUCAGGGGGCCACCCCUAAUAACAACGGGGCUUAGAAACCUCGUAUUUACCUUUCUAACCUCUGUGGUGGAGACAGGUGGGAGAGAAAAGUCCUGGGAAGUGGAUGAUGGAGGCAGCUAGCCGUAGCUGCUGCUUUUCUCUUCAAGCUCUUGGGAGAAUUGCUUGUGCUCCCUAUUCCCUUGGUGGAUGAUGGAGGCAGCUAGCCGUAUCUGCUGCUUUUCUCCUUCAAGCUCUUGGGAGAAUCGCUUGUGCUCCCUAUUCCCUUGGUGGCAGCUCACACCUCAGACCUGCUGUCCGCCCCCACUGCUUCACAGAACCCACUGCAACCACUGUCCAAGGUACUACCUCUGGUGUCGUCUCUCUUCAUCCCCAGGACUGUGAAGCCUGCUAACCUCUUUGCAGAGCUCCAUCUCCUUGCAUUGUGGGGUUCCUUCUAACUCUUCAGGGACUUCUCAACCUCCCGUCACCCUUCCUAAAUGCUGGGGUCCUAGAGUCCACCUUGUGCUCCACGCCCUCCCCAGGUGUCAUCUACAUCCCUAGCUUUGUGCUGCUCACCACCAAAUCAGUCUGGUGCUUCUGAGAUUUGGGCUUCAGACCCAAACAACUGCUGUGUGCUACUGGGCAACUCCCCGAGGUGUGCCGAAAGCUCCCCAAACCCAGCCUACCCCAAACAAAACUCAUUUUCCACCCAGACUAGUCUCUGCUUCCCUGAUCCCUUUCCUGGAGGCUGUUUCCACUUGCCAUCCCAUCAUGGAAGCCAGAAAACCAGUCUUCUUGACCUCUCCCCUUCCCCACUCCAUGGAGUUAGAGGUCCUGUUGAUUUUGCCAUGUAAACAUUUCGGAUUUGCUUACUUCAUCCCCACUGCCACCAACAGUGCAGGAUGGCCCUAAGAGGAGAAGUAAUGUGCUACCAAGUGGCCCAGCCAGAGUGUGAACCAAACAGUCUGGUACCAAAACCCUAUUCUGGAUCAUUCCUCCUUUCUGCUCCACCAGCAGUUUGGGGCACAGGCUUGGGAAUCCAGACAGGAAAGCUCCUCCCCUCUGAAGCAGUGGGACCAAAAAUGACAGCAUGGUUCUAGACAGCUCUGGAAGUCAGGCCUGUGAUUGCCUCAUUCCCUCCACCUUGGCCCCCAAAAUGGCCAGUCCUGAAGGGGUCACAGUUGAUACUUCUCUGAGGGGGCAUGGGGUUGGCUGAGGUUAUAGCAGCCCCACAGGGUGGUAAGCUGGGAUGAAGCAAUCAACUGGAACUCAACAAGCCUUGAGUUCUCAAAGGGGGUGUGGGAAGGUUCUUAUACAUCUUCUAUGAAGGGCAGUUUAUCAGUCACUAAAUUACAAAUACAUAAACCCUUUGUCUCACCAAACCUGCUGGGAAUGAAUCCUACAUAUAUAUUUAUAUGUGUGCAGGCUACAUGGUUUUCAUUAUGCUAUUGAUUUUAAAAGUAAAAAUUUGGAAAGAACCUCCAUGUCCACCAUGGGGAACUGGCUAAGUCAUUUAUGGUGGAAUGGUGAUCAUAAAAAUUCAUUAAAAAUGAAGACUCUAUAUACAGCUUGAAUAUUCCUUAUCGAAAUGCUUGGGACCAGAAGUGUUUCAGAUCUUUGCAUAUUUUCUGUUUCUCAUUUCAGUUCACAUUUUCUAAGCAUGAUAUUCCUACUGAUUUCCUUGUAGAUAUUUUGAAACAGAUAAGAAACUCCUCCGUGGAAAUUACUGUUAACUAGGGAAAAGACAUGUUUUUUUCUGUUCAUAAAAGUAAUGCGAGUUCUUUGUAGCAAAACUUGGAAAAUGCAUAAAAGUAAAAAAAAAAUGAAAACUUGUGUAAAAUUCCUCAUACUUUAGCCAUCCAUAGAUGGUCCUUACCAUUAGGAUUUUACUAAUUUUCCUUGCAGCUUUUUCUUAAAAUAUACACGUGUGUCUACACAUACAUAGUGUACACUAAAUUUUACAUACACACAGAGGAAUAUAUAUGUGUAUAGUUAUCUUGUGUUUAGAAAUUUGGAAUCCCUUCUAGUUGUCUUGUAACAUGUGCUUACUCUAUUUUGAGGAUUUUCUCUAUGAAUUUCAUGUAGCUCUUUAAAUUAACUUUCAGGAGGAUUGUAACAAUGUGCUCUCCACCCAGUAUUUUACCAGCCUUGAGUUUUCUCAAAGGGGGCAUUGGAGGGGUUCUUAUACAUUUACAGUGGGAAUGUGAAUUGAUACAACUUCUGUGGAGGGCAGUUUAUCAGCCACUAUCUAAAUUACACAUACAUAAACCCUUUGUCUAAGCAAACUUGCUGGGAAUAAAUCCUACACAUAUA